GUGACCGCUUCAGGGCAGUUGGUAGAUGCCCCUCUGGGAGAGAUCCCCAGGGGUGACAGCCAUGGACCCUGGAAGGGCCUGGGCUAGGGACAGGGACCAGAGCCAGUCCAGGGAGAGGACAGAGCCAAUGGACUGGGGUGUACUGUAACAGCCCUGCUGGCGAGAGGGACCAGGGCACCGUCCUCCAGGGAGCCCAUGCUGCAAGUCGGGCCAGAGGUGCCCCUGAACCUGAAGGCCAAUGAGACCCAAGACAGGCCAAGUGGGUUGUGAGACCCCUGAGGAGCUGGGCCCUGGUCCCAGGCAGCGCUGGCCCCUGCUGCUGCUGGGUCUGGCCAUGGUCGCCCAUGGCCUGCUGCGCCCAAUGGUUGCACCGCAAAGCGGGGACCCAGACCCUGGAGCCUCAGUUGGAAGCAGCCGAUCCAGCCUGCGGAGCCUGUGGGGCAGGCUCCUGCUCCAGCCCAGCCCCCAGAGAGCAGACCCCAGGUGCUGGCCCCGGGGGUUUUGGUCUGAGCCUCAGUCACUGUGUUAUGUCUUCGGAACUGGGACCAAGGUCACCGUCCUAGGUCAGCCCAAGGCCAACCCCACUGUCACUCUGUUCCCGCCCUCCUCUGAGGAGCUCCAAGCCAACAAGGCCACACUAGUGUGUCUGAUCAGUGACUUCUACCCGGGAGCUGUGACAGUGGCCUGGAAGGCAGAUGGCAGCCCCGUCAAGGCGGGAGUGGAGACCACCAAACCCUCCAAACAGAGCAACAACAAGUACGCGGCCAGCAGCUACCUGAGCCUGACGCCCGAGCAGUGGAAGUCCCACAGAAGCUACAGCUGCCAGGUCACGCAUGAAGGGAGCACCGUGGAGAAGACAGUGGCCCCUACAGAAUGUUCAUAGGUUCCCAACUCUAACCCCACCCACGGGAGCCUGGAGCUGCAGGAUCCCAGGGGAGGGGUCUCUCUCCCCAUCCCAAGUCAUCCAGCCCUUCUCCCUGCACUCAUGAAACCCCAAUAAAUAUCCUCAUUGACAACCAGAAAUCUUGUUUUAUCUCAUUUUUUUUCUCACAUAAAUUGCUAGCCUCCCCGGGGUUCUCAGUGUGGGGUACAGGGAAUUCUGCACCCAGUGUGAAAAUCACCCAAGGGAGGAGGCUCACAGCCUCCCUGAGUCAUCUCCCCAGAGGGUCCUUCCUCUCCCAGUCACCCCUUCUCCAACUCUCCACUGUACCCCUGAGCUACCAGUCUGGCAUCAGUUCAGACCAGUCCCACACCCUCCUAAAUUUUACUUCUCAAUAAAUACCUGAUCAUGUAAAACGCA